AAACCGGUGCCAACGUGCGCGGACGCCGCCGCCGCCGCCGCCGCUGGAGUCCGCCGGGCAGAGCCGGCCGCGGAGCCCGGAGCAGGCGGAGGGAAGUGCCCCUAGAACCAGCUCAGCCAGCGGCGCUUGCACAGAGCGGCCGGACGAAGAGCAGCGAGAGGAGGAGGGGAGAGCGGCUCGUCCACGCGCCCUGCGCCGCCGCCGGCCCGGGAAGGCAGCGAGGAGCCGGCGCCUCCCGCGCCCCGCGGUCGCCCUGGAGUAAUUUCGGAUGCCCAGCCGCGGCCGCCUUCCCCAGUAGACCCGGGAGAGGAGUUGCGGCCAACUUGUGUGCCUUUCUUCCGCCCCGGUGGGAGCCGGCGCUGCGCGAAGGGCUCUCCCGGCGGCUCAUGCUGCCGGCCCUGCGCCUGCCCAGCCUCGGGUGAGCCGCCUCCGGAGAGACGGGGGAGCGCGGCGGCGCCGCGGGCUCGGCGUGCUCUCCUCCGGGGACGCGGGACGAAGCAGCAGCCCCGGGCGCGCGCCAGAGGCAUGGAGCGCUGCCCCAGCCUAGGGGUCACCCUCUACGCCCUGGUGGUGGUCCUGGGGCUGCGGGCGACACCGGCCGGCGGCCAGCACUAUCUCCACAUCCGCCCGGCACCCAGCGACAACCUGCCCCUGGUGGACCUCAUCGAACACCCAGACCCUAUCUUUGACCCCAAGGAAAAGGAUCUGAACGAGACGCUGCUGCGCUCGCUGCUCGGGGGCCACUACGACCCAGGCUUCAUGGCCACCUCGCCCCCCGAGGACCGGCCCGGCGGGGGCGGGGGUGCAGCUGGGGGCGCGGAGGACCUGGCGGAGCUGGACCAGCUGCUGCGGCAGCGGCCGUCGGGGGCCAUGCCGAGCGAGAUCAAAGGGCUAGAGUUCUCCGAGGGCUUGGCCCAGGGCAAGAAGCAGCGCCUAAGCAAGAAGCUGCGGAGGAAGUUACAGAUGUGGCUGUGGUCGCAGACAUUCUGCCCCGUGCUGUACGCGUGGAACGACCUGGGCAGCCGCUUUUGGCCGCGCUACGUGAAGGUGGGCAGCUGCUUCAGUAAGCGCUCGUGCUCCGUGCCCGAGGGCAUGGUGUGCAAGCCGUCCAAGUCCGUGCACCUCACGGUGCUGCGGUGGCGCUGUCAGCGGCGCGGGGGCCAGCGCUGCGGCUGGAUUCCCAUCCAGUACCCCAUCAUUUCCGAGUGCAAGUGCUCGUGCUAGAACUCGGGGGCCCCCUGCCCGCACCCGGACACUUGAUCGAUCCCCACCGACGCCCCCUGCACCGCCUCCAACCAGUUCCACCACCCUCUAGCGAGGGUUUUCAAUGAACUUUUUUUUUUUUUUUUUUUUUUUUUUCUGGGCUACAGAGACCUAGCUUUCUGGUUCCUGUAAUGCACUGUUUAACUGUGUAGGAAUGUAUAUGUGUGUGUAUAUACGGUCCCAGUUUUAAUUUACUUAUUAAAAGGUCAGUAUUAUACGUUAAAAGUUACCGGCUUCUACUGUAUUUUUAAAAAAAAGUAAGCAAAAGAAAAAAAAAAGAACAGAGAAAAGAGAGACUUAUUCUGGUUGUUGCUAAUAAUGUUAACCUGCUAUUUAUAUUCCAGUGCCCUUCGCAUGGCGAAGCAGGGGGGAAAAGUUAUUUUUUUCUUGAAGUACAAAGAGACGGGGGAACUUUUGUAGAGGACUUUUUAAAAGCUAUUUUCCAUUCUUCGGAAAGUGUUUUGGUUUUCCUUGGACCUCGAAGAAGCUAUAGAGUUCAAUGUUAUUUUACAGUUAUUGUAAAUAUAGAGAACAAAUGGAAUGACUAAUCAUUGUAAAUUAAGAGUAUCUGCUAUUUAUUCUUUAUAAUAUCCCGUGUAGUAAAUGAGAAAGAAGUGCAGAGCAGGAUUAAAGAAAACCACUAAAACCGA